AUGCUCCGCUGCAGGCCCGCGCCCGCGCCCGGACUUUGCCAUCGGCGGGGCAGUCGCGGGAUGCGCCCGGGAGCCACAGCCUGAGGGUUUAAAAAGCUAUUUUAAGGCCGGGCUCGGUGUCUCACGCGUGUAAUCCCAGCACUUUGGGAGGCCCGAGGCCCUCAGGUCUCUGCAGGUGUCGUGGAGGAACCUAGCACCUGCCAUCCUCUUCCCCAAUUUGCCACUUCCAGCAGCUUUAGCCCAUGAGGAGGAUGUGACCGGGACUGAGUCAGGAGCCCUCUGGAAGCAUGGAGACUGUGGUGAUUGUUGCCAUAGGUGUGCUGGCCACCAUCUUUCUGGCUUCGUUUGCAGCCUUGGUGCUGGUUUGCAGGCAGCGCUACUGCCGGCCGCGAGACCUGCUGCAGCGCUAUGAUUCUAAGCCCAUUGUGGACCUCAUUGGUGCCAUGGAGACCCAGUCUGAGCCCUCUGAGUUAGAACUGGACGAUGUCGUUAUCACCAACCCCCACAUUGAGGCCAUUCUGGAGAAUGAAGACUGGAUCGAAGAUGCCUCGGGUCUCAUGUCCCACUGCAUUGCCAUCUUGAAGAUUUGUCACACUCUGACAGAGAAGCUUGUUGCCAUGACAAUGGGCUCUGGGGCCAAGAUGAAGACUUCAGCCAGUGUCAGCGACAUCAUUGUGGUGGCCAAGCGGAUCAGCCCCAGGGUGGAUGAUGUUGUGAAGUCGAUGUACCCUCCGUUGGACCCCAAACUCCUGGACGCACGGACGACUGCCCUGCUCCUGUCUGUCAGUCACCUGGUGCUGGUGACAAGGAAUGCCUGCCAUCUGACGGGAGGCCUGGACUGGAUUGACCAGUCUCUGUCGGCUGCUGAGGAGCAUUUGGAAGUCCUUCGAGAAGCAGCCCUAGCUUCUGAGCCAGAUAAAGGCCUCCCAGGCCCUGAAGGCUUCCUGCAGGAGCAGUCUGCAAUUUAGUGCCUACAGGCCAGCAGCUAGCCAUGAAGGCCCCUGCCGCCAUCCCUGGAUGGCUCAGCUUAGCCUUCUACUUUUUCCUAUAGAGUUAGUUGUUCUCCACGGCUGGAGAGUUCAGCUGUGUGUGCAUAGUAAAGCAGGAGAUCCCCGUCAGUUUAUGCCUCUUUUGCAGUUGCAAACUGUGGCUGGUGAGUGGCAGUCUAAUACUACAGUUAGGGGAGAUGCCAUUCACUCUCUGCAAGAGGAGUAUUGAAAACUGGUGGACUGUCAGCUUUAUUUAGCUCACCUAGUGUUUUCAAGAAAAUUGAGCCACCGUCUAAGAAAUCAAGAGGUUUCACAUUAAAAUUAGAAUUUCUGGCCUCUCUCGAUCGGUCAGAAUGUGUGGCAAUUCUGAUCUGCAUUUUCAGAAGAGGACAAUCAAUUGAAACUAAGUAGGGGUUUCUUCUUUUGGCAAGACUUGUACUCUCUCACCUGGCCUGUUUCAUUUAUUUGUAUUAUCUGCCUGGUCCCUGAGGCGUCUGGGUCUCUCCUCUCCCUUGCAGGUUUGGGUUUGAAGCUGAGGAACUACAAAGUUGAUGAUUUCUUUUUUAUCUUUAUGCCUGCAAUUUUACCUAGCUACCACUAGGUGGAUAGUAAAUUUAUACUUAUGUUUCCCUCAAGUGUGUAGUUAUUGAGUCAAAUUCAUAUGCAUGGUGUAUUGUGGGACAUACUUAGAUGGAAGGAGAGAGCCUAAGAAUCCUGAGGAUGAUUUCUGUGUAUGCCUCAAAAUGAGAUAUUUAGGCUGGGCGCGGUGGCUCACACCUGUAAUCCUCGCACUUUGGGAGGCUAAGGUGGGUGGAUUGCUUGAGCCCAGGAGUUUGAGACCAGCCUGGGCAACAUGGUGAAACCUCAUCUCUACACAAACUACAAAAAUUAGCUGGGCAUGGUGACACGUGCGGCUGCUUGGUAGGCUGAGGUGGGAGGAUCGCUUGAGCCCAGGAGGUGAAGGUUGCAGUGAGCCCUGAUUGUGCCACUGCAUUCCAGCCUGGGCGACAGAGUGAGACCAUGUCUCCAAAACAUACAUAUAUAUAAAAUAUAUUUAAAGACCUCUUGGAGUUCAGGCAGAAGUGAAGAUAGCACUAUGAAGUAGUUUCCACAUUAACAAUAGCAAUGACUUGAACGAUGUGUUCCCCCUUUCUUCUGAUAUUAAUAUCUGUUCAUUUUGCAAACAUUGAAAGAUUAUGAAAGCUAUGACCCAGAAUCACAAUUAUAUAAUUUGGAUACAUACCCAAAUGGCAUAAUUUCUGUCAUAAGCCUGUAGGAAAAGCUUGAAUUCUUCACUUCUCAGAUUCUCAGAGCCAGCUUGCUCUUGGGAGAGGGGCCUGGUAUAGGGGCUGCCCAGGUUCGUAGCCUAUGCUGUCAAGCAUGUUUGGAGUUGCACAUCUGUUCCCAUGUCAUUUUCUCUGUCUAACUGAAGUCAGAAAAUUCCUCAGCUGGAUUCUGGGGAACCAGGAACCCAUAUUCCCAAAUCCAAGAUUGGGACCUGGUUUGUCUUUCCAUUUGGGCACAUUUCAUUCUUUCCAGGAAAACAGGCCACUUCCAACCUGCACAAUGUACACCAAACCACAGAACCACAGCUGGGAUAUGGAGUCAGGAGAGGGAAGCUGGAGCUCAACUCUCAUGGACUAAAGGAUGGAUUCUGGAUGGGCUCCAGGGGACACCUUAUUGGAUUGGUGGCUUCCAUCAACUCUUAAAAACGUUAAGUGGUGAACUUUCCCGUCCUGUCAAGCUGUGAAUGGGGAAUGUAUACAAAGUCACUUUGACUUUUCUAUUUGAGGCCUCCACAGUAAACAUCCAGAGUCAUCCUAUUUUUGUCUUUUUACCUCCCUUUCAGAACCUGUUUUCGUAAUUAGACUGGAAAGCAAUUCAUGCUAAGUUUGCAAUGGCUGCCACAGUUGUAAGUGUCCCCUGCAUUUUAACCUGCACUAGAGCCCUAAGCCACAGAGAAGCAGUUCUGAAUUGGUAUCUCAAAUACCAUCCACCUGGUGUGGGUCUGCAGGGUGGAGAGCUUUCCCAGCACCCCUGAAGCAAUGCCCAAUGUCGAUUACCUUCUCUGAGUCCUGGCAAGUCCUGGCACAUUGGCUUUCUGGAUCCCUUAGAUGCUGCCCUUUCUGUUGUGAGGAGAGGUUGCCGAAGAUAUUGGAGGUGUCUGCUGGACUGUAGGAUUUCUGAUCCCACUGCUGUGUAGUUUUUUUUUCUAGUGCUGGACAAGUAAGAAGCCUCUGGAUAAAUUUGGUGUUGGUGGCUGAUGGUUGAAGUGGAAGCAGUCUUUGGGGUAGGAGGCAAUGCCACUCCUCUAGGCCCUUCGGGAGUUGGCUGAAGUUACUUCCUCCCUUGGAAGGGGCUGGUUAGUGAGUGCCAGGGAUCUCAGGACUGUCUCUGUGCCAGGUGUGGUUUCCCAGGCAACAGACACAUUCCUAAGUGCCUAGUUCUCUAGCGUCUGUAUACAUGGUAGUAGAGCCUUCCUUCCAUGUCUCUCUUCCCUCUGGCCUGGAAUAGGAGCAUUAGACUCAAAUUCUGAUGAAAAAGAAAUUACUUGGAGAUAGAGAUUCAAUGUGAAGAGAACAAGAUAUUUGAAGUCAGAAUUAGGUUUGAAUUUGGGCUCAGUGACUUACAGUGUGAGCUUGGUCAAGUUCUUAACAUUCUGGUCCUUAGCAUUCUCAUCUGUAUGGUCAAGGCUAUUGUCAUUGGGUUGGUAUGUCAACAAGCAAAACGGUAUGUGUGAGCUGCCCAAUUGUGGGCCUGGUUCUGAUUAGCCAAUGUUAACACCCUUCUCUCCACAGCUUCCCAUUCUCUGAUGCCGCUGACCCAGAUGGCGUCACCUCAGUUACCAUGGCUUGGUCCAAGCAGUGACUUCUGUUCAUGGGCUCUGGAAUUGAGUGGCCAAAAAUCUGGAAUCCCUACAGUAGGGAGAGUAGCCUUGUCCCUGCCCCACUACAAGUCUGUUCAUAUGAAGACAUACAAAGCCGUCGCCUCUAAUCAGUGUUCAAAGGGUCGAUUGUGCAACUCACAUUCCUCCAGAGAAAUUCCCCCAGCUUGUGAGAUCUCCAAGAGGGAACACGUAUUCCUGGCAUCCAACUUCCCCUGGUGCUCCCCCUGACCUGCCUCAUUCCAGGAGUUCCCUCUCCAGAGACCCUGUGUGCCCACACGAGCAGACUUUUAGAAAAUGGCCUACAGUUCAAAGGCCCUGCAUUGCUUUAUGGCCUUGGAAAUGUGGGGAAAGUGUCAGAUGAAGAAUUUCUAUCCUCCUCACCUCCUCCCUGUCUCCAAUAAAUGCAUACCAAGA